AGCCCACACUGCGGAGCCAGGCGGCAGCAUGGACCGGGCUGGGGCAGACAUGUGGGCCAGCACCUUCACCCUGGCCAUGGCCGAGAGGAAGCCCCAGGACGUCUGGGUUCUGCUACCUGAGCACAGCCUGGUCCCGGGAUGCCUGGACGGCGGUGGUGUCCAGUACCUGCUGGUGGGGCUCUCGAGGCUCCAGUGCGGUCACUGUCCGGGGACCUGGGACUCGGCCCAUGUGCACGUCCUCUUCCACCUGUGGUGGGACAGGGCCAGCCACCGGGGGCUGGUGAAGAUGCGCAUCUGGGGCCAGCGGUGCAGGCUGUGCCCCGCACCCGGGGACUGCCAGGUGAGGCCCCCGGGCGAGCAGCCCUUCCUCAGCAGGCUGGUCUUGCACAUCCUGCAGGACUGCUACGGGGAUGGCCCCGGCCCAGCCCGGCACCCCAGGGAGGCCUAUGAGGGCUGCUGUGAGGCCUGUGAGCUGGGGGUCUGCUUCCUCCAGAAGGCCCCAGACCCCGCCUGGAGCGCCAACGCCACAAAAGGCAACUUCCCCGCCACGGCCUGGGGUGGCACUGGCACCGUCUCCAGGGGCAAACCGCUGUCCACCCCUGGCGACGACCUUGGCAAGGGUGGCGUUGUCAUCGCCAUCCCCUUCUCCCUUGUGGGUACCAGCAAUGACCAGGUGCCCAUCGCUGAGGGCCCUGCCCCCCCUGCGGGGGCCUCUCUCCCUGUGACUGGCAGCUGUGAGGCCCUGGUCAUCGGCCAGGGCUCCAUCUUCCUGUCUGGGGAUUCAGUGGCCAUGCCUGGGGGCAAAGGCUUCCCGGUGGCCAUUGGAGACCCCCUCUUCCACGGCCCCGGCCUCCUCGGCAGCAGCAUCCAGACCUUCGAGCUCAAGGGCUUCCUCUUCAAAGGCCGGGGCUCCCUCUGCAGCCCGGUUGGCGUGGCCCAGGGCUGGGGCCCCAUCUCCCUCAACAAUGGCCUCGUCCCUGUGGGGAAACACACGCCAACCGUGUUCUACUGUGUGGGCCUCUCGGCCAGCGGGGAGGGCUCCCUCACCUUCCCCUCCUCCCUCACCAGCAUCUUCACCAACACCCUCUCGGAGCCCACCGAUGGCCCUGUGGCCACUAAAGAGGCCUCCAUCACCUUCCCCUUCAUCUUUACUGAUGUCAAGGAUGCCGUUGCUGAGGUGGCUGAAGGCAACGGGAAGGAAGGAGGCGGCCAGGGCCUCGUCCCAGUGGGUCACGACGCCCUGCCAGAGACCAAUGCUGGUGGCCUCCCCUCCCAGGUCAAGGGCUCCCUUGCCCUCCCCUUCCCUGCUGAUGUCCAAGGCAAAGAUGCCUUUACUGACAUCACUGAAGGCAAAGAGAAGGAAGGUGGCCUGGUCACCGCGGGUCACGACGCCCCUCUGGAGGCCAAUGCCGAGGGCCCCAUCACGGUUAGUGAGGGCUGCAUCACCAUCCCCUUCGCAGUCUUCGAUGUCAUAAAGCGCAAGGGCGGUGGCCACGUUGCCUACGGCCCCCAGGGCAAUGGCUGCUUCUCCCAAGGCUAUUACCAGAAGAGGCAGCUGAGGUCCAGGUUCCACAAGGCCCGCUGUGGGUGCCGCCGGGAGGAAGACGAGCGCCCUGGCCGUGCCUGCCGUAGGCCGCACGCCGAGCCCUACGAGGACUUCUGGAUCUGGGUGUCCAUGACCGUGUGCGUCUUCUGGCUGAUGUGCAUGUGUCGGCUGAACCCCGGGAUCUACCCGCAGCAAGUGUGACGCCCCGAAGUUCAGGCAACCCUCGCCUCUGGGACCCCGCCUCGCCUCUGAGACACCCCCCAACCCCGCCUUUGAGAUGCCCGCCCCGCCUCCGAGACCCCGCCUCCACCUCCGAGACCCCUUUCUCUGAGACCCCCGCCUCUGAGGCCCCGCCCCCCGCCUCCGAGACCCCGCCCUGCCUCUGAGACCCCGCCUCACCUCUGAGACACCCCCCAACCCCACCUUUGAGAUGCCCGCCCCGCCUCCGUGGCCCCGCCUCCACCUCCGAGACCCCGCCUCCACCUCCGAGACCCCUUUCUCUGAGACCCCUGCCUCUGAAGCCCCGCCCCCCGCCUCCGAGACCCCGCUUCACCUCCGAGGCCCCGCCCCCCGCCUCCGAGACCCCGCCCCCCGCCUCCGAGACCCCGCCUCACCUCUGAGACCCCGCCCCCGCCAGCAGCUCAGCCCCUCCUGUCUCUUGCCCCUGGUUUUGUGGGUCUGCCCUGAGCUGUGCCUGUGUGCUCCAGCCUCUUCCUAUGUGUGUAACUUCAAUAAAACCAAGCAAAGCCA